AGUCCCCAGAAGGAGCCAGCAUGGACAAUCUCCUUUACAGUUUCGGAAGCAGGUUUGUUGCCAUGGAGUUCACAUUUUGACGGGAGUUGAGAAGUAUAAAGGUAACCAUUUGUUUUAGUUUCAACGAUCUGACAAAAAGAUAGGCUGUUGCUCUUCUUCUGGAAAAGCCUGAUUGGUAAGAUUCCUUUAAGGGCUCAGCCCCAAAGAGCUUUAUCCCAUCCCCUCGCAGACUGAAAACUAAAGCCUGCAGAGACCUCUGAAGGAAAACCUGUCCCGGGCUCUGUCACUUCACACCCAUGGCUAACCCUGGAGGUGGUGCUGUUUGCAACGGGAAACUUCACAAUCACAAGAAACAGAGCAAUGGCUCACAAAGCAGAAACUGCACAAAGAAUGGAAUAGUGAAGGAAGCCCAGCAAAAUGGGAAGCCACAUUUUUAUGAUAAGCUCAUUGUUGAAUCGUUUGAGGAAGCACCCCUUCAUGUUAUGGUUUUCACUUACAUGGGAUAUGGAAUUGGAACCCUGUUUGGCUAUCUCAGAGACUUUUUAAGAAACUGGGGAAUAGAAAAAUGCAACGCAGCUGUGGAAAGAAAAGAACAAAAAGAUUUUGUGCCACUGUAUCAAGACUUUGAAAAUUUUUAUACAAGAAACCUUUACAUGCGAAUCAGAGACAACUGGAACCGGCCCAUCUGCAGUGCCCCAGGGCCUCUGUUUGAUUUGAUGGAGAGGGUAUCAGACGACUAUAACUGGACGUUUAGGUUUACUGGAAGAGUCAUCAAAGAUGUCAUCAACAUGGGCUCCUAUAACUUCCUUGGUCUUGCAGCCAAGUAUGAUGAGUCUAUGAGGACAAUAAAGGAUGUUUUAGAGGUGUAUGGCACAGGCGUGGCCAGCACCAGGCAUGAAAUGGGCACCUUGGAUAAGCACAAGGAGUUGGAGGACCUUGUGGCUAAGUUCCUGAAUGUGGAAGCAGCUAUGGUCUUUGGGAUGGGAUUCGCAACUAACUCAAUGAAUAUCCCAGCAUUAGUUGGAAAGGGAUGCCUCAUUUUAAGUGAUGAGUUAAACCACACAUCGCUUGUGCUUGGGGCCCGACUCUCAGGUGCAACCAUAAGAAUCUUCAAACACAACAACACACAAAGCCUAGAGAAGCUCCUGAGAGAUGCUGUCAUCUAUGGCCAGCCUCGAACCCGCAGAGCUUGGAAAAAGAUUCUCAUCCUGGUGGAGGGUGUCUACAGCAUGGAAGGUUCCAUCGUGCAUCUGCCCCAGAUCAUAGCUCUAAAGAAGAAAUACAAGGCUUACCUCUACAUAGAUGAAGCUCACAGUAUUGGGGCCGUGGGCCCAACCGGCCGGGGUGUCACGGAGUUCUUUGGACUAGACCCUCAUGAAGUUGAUGUGCUCAUGGGCACAUUCACCAAAAGUUUUGGAGCUUCAGGAGGUUACAUAGCUGGAAGGAAGGACCUCGUGGAUUAUUUACGGGUUCACUCGCAUAGUGCUGUUUAUGCUUCAUCCAUGAGCCCACCGAUAGCAGAGCAAAUCAUCAGAUCACUAAAACUUAUCAUGGGACUGGAUGGGACCACUCAAGGGCUGCAGAGAGUACAGCAACUUGCGAAAAACACAAGAUACUUCAGACAAAGACUGCAGGAAAUGGGAUUCAUUAUCUAUGGCAAUGAGAAUGCUUCUGUUGUUCCUCUGCUUCUUUAUAUGCCUGGUAAAGUAGCGGCUUUUGCAAGGCAUAUGCUAGAGAAAAAAAUUGGAGUGGUGGUCGUGGGAUUUCCAGCCACUCCCCUCGCAGAAGCUCGGGCUCGGUUUUGUGUUUCAGCGGCACAUACCCGGGAGAUGUUAGACACGGUUUUAGAAGCUCUUGAUGAAAUGGGUGAUCUCUUGCAACUGAAAUAUUCCCGGCACAAGAAGUCAGCACGUCCUGAGCUCUAUGAUGAGACGAGCUUUGAACUCGAAGAUUAAGUUUCCUGGUCCUGAAUGACACAUAAAGACUUUGCGAGAAAGACCUCCCUCCUUGCCUCACAAGGAAUAUAAAUGGAUUUCUCCCCCUUCCUCAGGACAAUUUUGGUUCCCAGACCAGCUUGAUUGAACUGAGGGAGACGUUGUUGUUUUUAAUGUCUCCAGCUUGGACUGCAGAGACAAAAACAUGAUUCCAGAUUUAAGUCUCUCUUCUUCCAAGUAUUCUACUAGAAAUACACACACACACACACACACACUUCUGAGAAUAUUUUUAAUGGCAAUAAGCCUGUGUUUUAGCUGCUACUGUGCAGACCCUUUCAGGGAUUCCAACCAAAUGCAAAUGAGAGAAUUUAAAAUUUUUAUUCAGUAAGUUCACUAUGUGUUUACUUAUUCCAUCUGCAGAUGUAAGUGAGUGUGGUGGACAGUAGCCACCUUCCUUGUUCCACUCAUAAAAGCAUCAGCUAGAUCUCAUCUGUAUCAUGGGAAGUUCCAGGCAGGAGGGUAAAGAAAUGUUGUUUCUACCAUUUGUCACAUUUGGACGUUUUUCACAGACAAGUGUCAAAAGACAUAGUUAAUGUUUCGAGGGGGAAAGCAGAACUGAUCAACUGCGACUAGAGACGUCUUUGAAGGAAAUUUUCCUUUUCCUCUUGCUGGUCUCCUACAGUUUUACAGCUGAGCUUUUGAGGUUUGGAAAAUUCAAGAUGUUUGUUUCAUAAGAAAAGGGGCAGAAAGCAAGCACAAGACACUUUUAGGUCUAGACUAAAAUGGUAGUUACAACAAUUUGAACCUUGUUGGUGCAGUGCACGGUGAAUGCUUACCCUGCACAGCCUCUAUUACCUUAAGGAAUUAGUUGUCAUUUUCCUAUUGAAUUUUGAGUAAAUGGUGAAAUUCAGUGUCCUUUAGAAUCGACUCCCAAGACUAUAUUUGAAGAAUGCAUUGAUUCAAGAAGGACAUUUAAAAGCAAAUUCUGACUUUUUCAAGACCAACACACUUGUUUAGGCCUAUUAAAUUGUACUAUCACUUGUUACAUGCCCUCUGAAUUGGGAGAAAGUGGGCUUGCACACUUUGAGGUAACUAACUGUAAUUUACUUGUGUUCUCUCUUUCUUGCUCUCCUUCUCAACAUGAACACAAACCUCUAUGGAAAAGUAGCCUCUUGUUAAUCUGAUCUAGUUUGUAUGGAAAAAGCCCAUGGAGAACCUUAUCUUUAACAAGCUCCCAGAGGGUGCCCAGAUUUGGAAAUUCUAGAGAGCAGUGGUGACCUUUUAGCAAAGCUUCUGUAACAGUUCGAAUGAGUUGCAGAACAUUCCACUCCAUCAAAUGACACUGUAAACAAAUCACUUCAAGAGAGGCUUGGUUUUGUGUGGCACAGAUGGACCCAAGCUUUCAUGCUGUGCACUGAGAUAGAAACUCCACCCGCAGCGCCUGCGAUGGAUGGAGCAGUGUGCCCUGAUGCUCAAAGCGUAUUAAAGGAAAAAAAGUGAUCAGCAUGGAAAGUUUUUAUGGGGAAAUUAUAACUCCAAGUGGGUGCAUUGGUUUAAAAAUGGAUCACAAUGAUAGAGUUCUUCAUGAAUGUUUACAAGUUGUAAGGAAUACCGUUAGUGAAAGAGGAAAAGAAGUGGGUUCUGAAAAUGCAGUUUCCCAUCCAAUGAUUUUGAUAACAAAAUUCCAACUUUUCUCAAUGAAACUGAUGCAGUAUUAUUUGUGCAAAUAAAAUGUGUCAUAAAUAUGCAAAGAAAGGGAGACAUACUGUUCUUAUCUUGAAUAUGUGCAUUUAAAUGAAUUGUCCAAAAUGCAUAAAUGCCUUGCGUUCUAUAAAGGAAACAGGAGGUCAAAAAGACAGCGAGAUAUCUAGUCCUUCCACAAGGUAUGGAAAGCAAUAAACAUCUUCCUUUCUUUCUGGAUCUGUCUGUGAUGUUUACACACACCUUCACAUCUACACUUCAAGUUUUAAGCCCCUAGACAUGUGUCUUCAUGAGCAGGAAUGUCCACUAUUAUUACUUUCAUGGAGGAUAUUGGGUCUAAUUCAUUGUGGGAAACUACUUACCUACCCAGCAUGGAAGGCAGGGAGGAAGUUAGUCUCUUUUCAUCAAGAUUCAAGAGUACAGGGGCAAUUUAUUACACUGCAAUGUACAAAACAAAAGGACCUGUUUCUGUUAGAGAGUCCAUGUUGAAUAUACAGGUAUGAGAACAACUGUUGAUAUACAGGUAUAAUCCAAGUAGAAUGCUUCCACAGUGCAUUAGAAGGUGCCCAAGCUCCACAGGGCCAAUAAUAUUAGAGUAUAUGUCAUAUAGAAUAAGGUUAAUUAGGAGGGUGAUUGUGAAUAAUGAGAUUUUUAAUUUUUUUAAGAAAAAGCUCUCAAAUGCUAGGCUAAUAAGUUCAUGAUUUUAAUUCAUGAUUUUAAUUCAUGAUUAAAAUUAUUUGAUUAUUGAGUCUUGAUAAUUAUAUCAUCAACCAUUACCCUCUACAUCACCGCCCCGACCUUAGCUCUAAUUAUAUCAGAGCCAAAAAUGUGUCUUUGGUUAGAUCUGUUGGAAAAGAGAAUUUUCUAUAAUGUUAUGCGCACUCAGCCCUUCUGUUCACAUUUACACACAUGCACACACACAUACACAUAUGCAUUUUUCCUUUACGGAGUAAGCAACUAUGAAAAUCUGGUUGGUUGAGAAAUAAAUGGAAGAUGUUCUUGAAAAUGACCUCAGGAAAGCAGAAGAUAAAGGUUCCAGAUGAUAUUUGUAAGGAGGCUAUCUCUGUAUAAUAAGGAAAUGGCAUAGACUUAUUCCUAAUCUCAUUAUGAAACGAUGGUGUCAUGGACGUUUAACCAUAUUGCCUUUCAGCAUGCUUUGAUUUUACAGAGACGACAGGCUUUGGAAUUUACUAGGAAGCUGGCUAAAAUCCAUACCCCUAGGCCCUACACCAGACCUUUACUGAAACAUAAUAGUUGUAGUGCCCAGGAAUCUACAUUUUUAACCAGCCUUCCUGCGUGAUUCUAAUCUAUGCCAAAAUUUAAGAACAUUAUUCAAACUCUAAUUUGAUAAACCAAUUGACUCUAAUAGCAGGAACCUUGUUCUGAUUCUCUUGUUCAUAAUUAAGUGUAUAUAUACUGGUAAAAUUAAUUUAUUCCACAGUCAACCUUCUCUUCUCAUUGGGACAUUUUGUUCCCAUUUUCCAAGUAACUUCUCUUUCUACAAAAAUUGAUCCAAUAUUGAAGAACCAUCUGCGAUUCAUUUGGGUAAAAUUAUGCCUUCUUCAGUUUUCUGUAUCAUUCCCUAUAAGAUGCCCAUUUGCUUUGAAUGUGGUAUCUUUCUUUUCUUUCUUUCUUUUUUUUUUUUUUUUUGAGACAGAGUUUUGUUCUUCUUGUUGCCCAGGCUAUAGUGCAAUGGCAAGAUCUCGGCUCAUUGCAACCUCCACCUCCCGGGUUCAAGCGAUUCUCCUGCCUCAGCCUCCUGAGGAGCUGAGUUUACAGGCAUGUGCCACCAAGCAUGGCUAAUUUUCUAUUUUUAGUAGAGACAAGGUUUUUCCCUGUUGGUCAGGCUGGUCUCGAACUCCUGACCUUAGGUGAUCCUCCCACCUCGGCCUCCCAAAGUGCUGGGAUUACAGGCGUGAGCCACCGUGCCCGGCCUGAAUGUAGUAUCUUUCUUCUGUUUUCUUUUCCUGCUCUUUAAAAAACAACCUUCAACCUCUGAUUAUUUAUUCCAACAACAGCUCUUCAGUAGGGUAAAAGUCUUAACAGUUCUUCAAACGAACAAUAUUCUUUUGUAUUUUUCUUCAGAGAUAGCAAAUGUUAUAAAUGGCCUACUCUGAUUUAAAAACCUAAGUUCCGAUGAUGAUGAAACAUUAACUCUUAAAUAUACAUUUUGAUUUAUAGCAAUAAUAACAAUUGUAACAACAGCAAUUAAGAACAGCAUCUGGUGAAUUCUUGGCAAUGUUUCCUGGUCUCAAAACAGUAAGAACAAUUUGAAGUCUGUUCUUUAGAAUGCCCUACUCAGCUGCAUAAUGUUUAGAAAAUUAAAGAGUCUGUAUUUUAAAUAUUUUUAGGUAAUUAUUGCGGGACAUUGUCUUAUGGUGUCCUGAUGUACGUGGGGUGUGCAUGUGUGUGUGUGUGUGUGUGCAUGUGUCUUUGUGUGUGUGAGAAGGACAGAGAGAAAUGUAUGUUUCACUGAAACAUUUGAAACGACCAAUUUCACUUUAUUGUGCCUGUAAAAUGUUAGUUUUAAAAUAAAUAAAAAUAAUAUGAAAAUAA